ACCUCUCCCUAUGGUGUGGCUGGCUAGCCCGGGGGUCUCUACGCUGCUUGGUCUUUGUUAACGGAGAUGAAGGCAGUAAUUUUUCAGUAACAGGUUUCAGAUAUAAGUCCCUUGGUGAUGCUAAUAUUUAUGGAGGCCUUACUAUGCAUUAAGAACUUUUUUAGAAGUUUAGAAAAUGGCAGUGAAUAAAGCAGAUACAAAUCUCUGCUCUAAGGGAGCUUGCAUAGUAAUGAAAUUUGAGAAGACAGUGGAUUGGAAGUGGGAUUAACUCAGAAUCAAAAUUUUGUCGAUGGGUUGGAGGAAGAGGAAGUUAUUUGGGACCAAAAAGACAUACAGGUGUGAGUUUAUUUGGGAGGGAGGAAGGAAUCCUCAUCAGAUGUGCAGGAAUGUUGGAAAAGCCUAAAGAUUAGACUGUAAGAAAAGAAAAUAGAAGCCAUGUUUCGAAGACCUGUAUUACAGGUACUUCGUCAGUUUGUAAGACAUGAGUCCGAAACAACUACCAGUUUGGUUCUUGAAAGAUCCCUGAAUCGUGUGCACUUACUUGGGCGAGUGGGUCAGGACCCUGUCUUGAGACAGGUGGAAGGAAAAAAUCCAGUCACAAUAUUUUCUCUAGCAACUAAUGAGAUGUGGCGAUCAGGGGAUAGUGAAGUUUACCAACUGGGUGAUGUCAGUCAAAAGACAACAUGGCACAGAAUAUCAGUAUUCCGGCCAGGCCUCAGAGACGUGGCAUAUCAAUAUGUGAAAAAGGGGUCUCGAAUUUAUUUGGAAGGGAAAAUAGACUAUGGUGAAUACAUGGAUAAAAAUAAUGUGAGGCGACAAGCAACAACAAUCAUAGCUGGUAAGA